ACUGAGCGCCGCGCCGUGGGCCGAGUGGGGCGGGGAGACCCAGCCCUCGGCGCGCACGGAGCCUGGCCGGUGCUGCAGCGCCGCCGAGUGCGGCCUCGGGGGCGGCGGCCGCGGGAGGGACCCGGAGAGCUGCUUCCCCUAGUCAGGCCGCGGCGUGGGAGGGCGAGACCCCGAGCAAACUUUCUAGCGGCUUCGGCCCGAGGGUGGUGACGCCCGGGGCUGGUCGCGGCGGCUGCGGCAGCGGGCUCCAUCCCCUGGCAAAUCCCCUUCCCGGGAGCAAGUGCCUUCAGCUGGGAGUGUCUGGAGCCCUGGCCACCAGCGGAGCUGCAUCCUGUGGCCCUAUAACACUCUUCUCCAAAAGGACCUGCCAGAGACUGGGAGUGUUGACUGCUGCAAGGACCAAGAACCGAGUAGCUACCUUAUAAAGACCAUCUGUACAUCCACUGUGAAAUGGAGUUUCAAAAUCACAAGCUUCUUUCCCACAUGAACAUAAGACUAGGAGCACAUAUGGAAGAGUAAAGUUGAAGGGAAUUUGGAUGAUGAUUUGGCAAGAUGCUGUAAGUGGAUUAGGCAAGGCUGCUAAAGAGAGACAGGAAAUGGCUGUGUUAGUGCUUCGGACCUCCGUUAGAAGUAGCAGUUCAUGGUGUUGAAGGUUUGUUGUUGAAAAUACCUUCCUGAGGCACCUCUUCAUUGUGCUUAUUCUUCCCACAACAUUGUGCCAAGACACUGUCAAGCCUGGGCCUGUCAAAGCCUGGGAUGUCAAAGGCCUGGGUCUUUCUCAUCCUGCUGUAAUGUAUUGAUAGCUGGGGGCUCUGCAGAAGGACAAGGGAAAGGUGGGAUAGUAACAUCUUUUUGAGGGAAGAAUUGGCUUCCUUUCUUGAAAGUGGUGAAGGUACAGCAUAUAGCUGCAUGGAAGAAACAGUAAUCGGAUGGCUACCUUCUACAUUUUGUAUUAGGAAACAAAGUCCAUUGUAAGAGUCCAUGUUGAUCUUGGAAAUAGAAGGAUUGAAAAAAGCUAAAUUUCCACAAAGAACAAGAACUUGACCAUCUCCUUUUUGAUCUGAAGACUAGGGGACAAUGGAUAUCAUAGAGACAGCAAAACUUGAAGAACAUUUGGAAAAUCAACCCAGUGAUCCUACGAACACUUAUGCAAGACCCGCUGAACCUGUUGAAGAAGAAAACAAAAAUGGCAAUGGUAAACCCAAGAGCUUAUCCAGUGGGCUGCGAAAAGGCACCAAAAAGUACCCGGACUAUAUCCAAAUUGCUAUGCCCACUGAAUCAAGGAACAAAUUUCCACUAGAGUGGUGGAAAACGGGCAUUGCCUUCAUAUAUGCAGUUUUCAACCUCGUCUUGACAACCGUCAUGAUCACAGUUGUACAUGAGAGGGUCCCUCCCAAGGAGCUUAGCCCUCCACUCCCAGACAAGUUUUUUGAUUACAUUGAUAGGGUGAAAUGGGCAUUUUCUGUAUCAGAAAUAAAUGGGAUUAUAUUAGUUGGAUUAUGGAUCACCCAGUGGCUGUUUCUGAGAUACAAGUCAAUAGUGGGACGCAGAUUCUGUUUUAUUAUUGGAACUUUAUACCUGUAUCGCUGCAUUACAAUGUAUGUUACUACUCUACCUGUGCCUGGAAUGCAUUUCCAGUGUGCUCCAAAGCUCAAUGGAGACUCUCAGGCAAAAGUUCAACGGAUUCUACGAUUGAUUUCUGGUGGUGGAUUGUCCAUAACUGGAUCACAUAUCUUAUGUGGAGACUUCCUCUUCAGCGGUCACACGGUUACGCUGACACUGACUUAUUUGUUCAUCAAAGAAUAUUCGCCUCGUCACUUCUGGUGGUAUCAUUUAAUCUGCUGGCUGCUGAGUGCUGCCGGGAUCAUCUGCAUUCUUGUAGCACACGAACACUACACUAUCGAUGUGAUCAUUGCUUAUUAUAUCACAACACGACUGUUUUGGUGGUACCAUUCAAUGGCCAAUGAAAAGAACUUGAAGGUCUCUUCACAGACUAAUUUCUUAUCUCGAGCAUGGUGGUUCCCCAUCUUUUAUUUUUUUGAGAAAAAUGUACAAGGCUCAAUUCCUUGCUGCUUCUCCUGGCCGCUGUCUUGGCCUCCUGGCUGCUUCAAAUCAUCAUGCAAAAAGUAUUCACGGGUUCAGAAGAUUGGUGAAGACAAUGAGAAAUCGACCUGAGGAGCAAAACAAAGGCAUCAGCUCUUACACCAAAAGAGUUAACGCUGUAACCAAAGGUAUAGUUUUGUUUUUUAUUUUAGGAGAACUGACUGGUAAAUGAAGAAAUGGACCAAAUUUUGUGUAAACGAUUAGAAAGAUGAACAAAGUAUUGCCCUUUGACUGGUUUUCUUCUUCAUCCUGAGAAAGAUACAUUCUCUUGCAGCUCUUCAUUCAUUGGUGACAAGCCCCCACCCCGGGACUUUACUAAUGAGCUUGUUAAAGAGGUGCCAAAGAACAUAUUCCUCCUUUCUUUAUUCUUUCUCCACCAAAACCCUCUACUUCAGAAUUUUUUCAGGAUAUUUUUCAGCCCAAGGUCAGAAGAAUGUGUUAAUAUUUUAAAUAAAAUAUCUGGACAUCUACAGCCACUGUGUAAAUAGAACUGCCUAAUGUUGAGAGUGGUUUUUAGCAUUAGGUUUAGCAAGGGGGAGAUCCGUGGGUUGUGCGUCAGCUUUGGGUGAAUUUUGUUUCUACCCUGUCACGGGGAAAGUUCGGGUUGAGUCCAGGAGUGCACACUGCUGCUGCCACCCAAUGCGCUACAUAUCACUUUUUUUUGUUUUGUUUUGUUUUGUUUUUAAAAGAUCAUUUUAUCUUAAAAAGGAAAGCUGAUCCAAGUAAACACGAAAGUAUUUGACACACCCCACAGAUUUUACAUGUGUGUAAAUGUUUCACUUUAAAAUCUCUAUGACAGAUACACAGGAAACAUGAGAUGGUUUCUGCUAAUGAGUGGCCCUUGAGUACACACUUAGAUGCUGUCUGCCCUGUAAAUUUGGAUCUGGUGCCCCAGGGCAGUCAACUCUUCUAGCACAGGCUGAAAACACGUGUGUGUCAACUGAGGUUCACACCACUUGGGGAAUGAGCCUGUUUUCUUUCCAGGUCAGGCCCUGGUGUGAGAUCAAUUUUAGGGCUCCUAAUUGGAGCACAGAAAUGUAUUUGGUCAAAUUUCAUUGAAGGUGAUUUCUUCCUUUUUCUGUUGUACUUUAUGGAAAAACCAAGAUGGAACCUGAAAGUUAAUGUAUCCUUGCUUUUAGCAAGAGACUCAGUUUCUUAUAACUAGUCCUAAGGACAUAUGCCGCAAUUGAGUAAUUUUACUUUUACCCUAUGAAAAUAACAUGGUGCUGCACUAUAAUAUACUCUCGGAAUCAGUGUGUUAGUUACAGCUAUACAGUGAAGGGGGAUAACUGUUUCUAAAUUUCUUUAAGGUGAUGCCAAAAAAUGGAUUAAAAAAUCUGAUCAGAUUUAAUGUUACCAGAUUUAGUGCAUUAUUUAAUGCUAUUGGAUCUUUUGGAUAAUUCUUGGCUUAAUUUCUUAGCUACUUGAAGGUUAAUUUGCAAGACUUUUAAAACCUUAGAAAAGUUUUAAGGUUGCAAAGUUAUCAACACUGGGGCAGAGGGUGGAGAGGCCAAUGCGGGUAGAAGGAGGCAGUUAUGUUUAUAUUGAAGGUGAAAUUUUUCUUUCAUUUAGAAUGGAAAACAUCCCCAAAUGUAUCAUUAUAAACUAGUCAGCCUUGACUACACAAAAUUGACCUUUAAGUUGCUUGAGAAAAACACAAUGCAAAUCGUUCAGAAGGGUCAACAUCCUUUGGUGCUAAAAUCUUGUGUAUGUUUUCAGAAUGGCUUUUUCUGUAUGUUAUAGAAUAAUCACUAAAGGAAAGGUAGUUGAAUUUAAAGUCAUGAAGCAAGACUCUUUAAUUCAGUUAUUUUAAACAAGAAUUAAAACCCCAAACAUCCUUGGCAGGCUUUGAAGCACACAGAAUUUUCUAGUAUUUCUUAUUAAAUACACCAAUAAUAAACAUAUACUUAGUUUACCUGAUGAGUUUAGACAUAAUUCUAUAUAAUGUUCGCUUAUAUUCAUUUAUUAACUAGCAACACUUGUGCAAGAACAAGGUAUUCUGCUUGAAAACACUGAUUUUUAAGUUCCUGUUGCCCGAUUGUAAAGAAAAUCAUCUGACACAGAAGCCUGGAUUUUGCUCUCCUAACACUGGUGUUUUCCUUGAGCCUCUAAUUCAAAUAAAACAAACUGAUACACCUUACAGCCUUAUUCAUCUGUGUCUGGAUAACUCACUUUUCAUCUAUUGAAUAAGAAAAAGUGUUUAAACUUAAUAAAAUAAAAAAUUGUGCACCAAUUACUACAGAUCCUUGAAACAGUAAGCCUUGGAUUUUAGUCAAGUAAUCCAGUUUUUUUUUAAUUUAAAAAAAACCAUCACCUUUUAAAGAACUUUAAAAACACCUGUGAUGCCAAUGUGGACAUUGCCGCUGCCAUGUCUUUACACGCAUGUGUCGUAUAGCUCUGUCAUCGAGUUGAGGAAGUCCAUGGUUUGCAAAUAAGGGUGGGGGAAUCAAAAUUUCAAGAUGGAAAAAUAAAACAAAUAGUAAAACCCAUUUACAUGUAGGAAAGAAAAGUUGAGCUUCAACCCAAUGUGCCACUUUGAUAUAAAACAAGUAUGAUAUAUAUAUAAACUGAAGAUAUAAAACAAGUAUGAUCUUGCCUUUGAAAUCAUAAAUGUUUGGGGUACCUGUUCUUUGCCAGUUAAGAUACAUAUCUUAUUAUCUUUGUUUUUUUCAAGUCUAUGCUCCUGUUUGAAGCUUUUCCUGUAAUUUAGGUUGUCUGUGAAAUACCUAUAACAUAUAAUUCCUAUAGAGUAUGCCACAUUUUUUUUCUAACUCAUUUCAAAUGAAAUUCUCUCAGAUUCUAGUUUUUGAGCUUGUCCACUAGAUCUGAAAAUAAAGCAUCCUUUCCUGAGUCCACUUGAACUAAUUGUGAAUUUGUUACUUAAUUUACUGGCAUCUUGGGAAACAAGUUUUGCUGUGGCAGGAAGGCUGUUUUGAGAGUGAGCGUUGAGUCUACUCUGGUUUGUGGAUGACAUUGCAUUAGGGUUAUUUCCUGUAUUACCAGUGCCCCCUUGUGGCAAUAUACUUUAUGACUUGGAAUGCAAACACCACUUUUAAAAGCCUGUUUUCAAGUUUUUGAAAGGCAUUUGUUUUCUGUUGUUUGCCAAUAAUCUGAAAGUAUCAUGUGAAAGGAAUUAUUUUAAAAGCAUUUUAAACCUUUCCCAAAGGUAAAAUGUGCUCAGAUUAUAGGCACUUGUAAUUCUAACCUUGUAUCCAUUUGAUCAAAGAAAAUUUGUAGAACAUUUUUACCUCUCAUGAUCACAAUCAUUAGUGUCUCCCUUUAUAACGACCUAUGUUUUGUUUACUUUGAAACACCAAAUUUGUUGUCUUGGUUUUUUUUACAUGACAGAACUCAUGCAGUUUCUUUUUUAGUUGAAAGUUCACAUCUUGCCCCUUGAAUAGUUUGAACAUUUCUUUCUUAAUUCUUUUUUGUUUUUGUUUUGCACUGUAAAACUGAUGAAAACUUUAAGCCAAUCUUAAUGCACUAGCCUCUGUAGUGUAAGGAAGUGUGAGAAGGAGUUUCUUAAUGAGUUUACACGUUUAAAUCAAGCAUAUUAUAAGUUAUAUGCCAUGUGUUGAAGGCUUUUCUAUUUAUAUAUAUAAAGAUUUUUAGUAUUUGUUUUUAGUGUCCUUGUGUUGCAAUAAUUUAACUCCUUUGACUCAGUUGCUGAAAAUAUUUCUUCUAUUAAGAAGUGCUCUUGACUUCAACACCCAAACACUGAAAAUCAUGUCAAUGUUACCCAAAGAUAAGUUUUUAUACAGAUACACACCUUAUAAGUUCUGAUUUAUUUUCUUACUCAUUAUGCUGUGUUCUAAAUAAAUCAUGAAUGAGAAGAGUGCUUUAUUGUGAAAUUAUUUAAAACUGUCCUUUAAAAGAAAAAGAGGAAACGAUGAACAAAAACUAAUCUAAUUGCCAAGUUAGAAUUCAUUAUUUAAUUUACCUCCUAUGCAAUGAUUAAUGCUGCAAAAUGUAUGGUUAUGUUACCGUAUAUUCACAAAAGAAAUAUUAUUACAAGGUUUCAGAGGUAGCCAAUUGCAUUCUUUUGGAAAUUUACUGUACUGUUUCAAUGUGUUAAGUGCCUUGUUGUAAAGUAAAAUUUUAAGUCUAGAUUCAUUAUUUUCCUGACAUAUAUUUUUCAUUAUGAUAUCUACUGUAUGCUAUUGUGAUAGUUUUAUGAAAUGCUUACAUUUUAAUCAAAUAUGUAAAUUUCAGAAGCUCUUUUUUCCUACCCACCAGUACCUUAAUCAUUGGUUUAUCACAUUGGAUUCAAAUUCAGGUUCCUUUUUUGAUAAAGAGGAAAUUUGUUUUCCAUGCUUGUGAUUUUGUGUUUGUAAACAUUUCAGGAGGAAUUUAGGAGUGUAACUAUAGUUUAUACUUCUAUAAUGUUGUCUUACAUUUACAUUUUUAAGUGCCUAAUUGUUAAAACUGAUUUAUGUUUCUCUUCUAAAGAGGAUAUGUGUACUUGGUUUCUAAUCUCUUUGGUUUUGCUUUUUAAAAAAUGCAAGAGCCUAUACUUUGUAUUUACCUAAUAAACCACAGUGACAUCAACAGUCUUUUCAAAAUUAA